GGAACUUCCGGCGUCCUCCUCGUGGCGGUCAUUUUGGCCUCUGUCCUGUUUGUCCAGCCCGCCAGUUUCUGCAGUGGAGGUCGCGACUGAGGGACGGGACAGAGAAGUCGCGAAAGUGGGCCAGAGGUUCUGCGACACCACCUCGGGUGAGCUGCGCCAGGCCCGGGAUAGGGACUGUUGUGUUCGAAUGCCCGCCCCGGUCGGCCGCCGCUCCCCGCCUAGUCCACGGAGCUCAAUGGCGGCAGUCGCGCUGAGGGACUCGGCUCAGGGUAUGACCUUUGAGGAUGUGGCCAUUUAUUUCUCCCAAGAAGAGUGGGAGCUCCUUGAUGAGUCUCAGAGGUUCCUGUACUGCGAUGUGAUGCUGGAGAACUUUGCACAUGUAACAUCCCUGGGUUAUUGCCAUGGAAUGGAGAAUGAGGCGAUAGCUUCUGAGCAGAGUGUAUCUAUACAGGUCAGGACUUCUAAGGGCAAUACACCCACCCAGAAAACUCACCUCAGUGAGAUUAAGAUGUGUGUCCCAGUCUUGAAAGACAUUUUGCCUGCGGCUGAGCACCAAACCACAUCCCCUGUGCAAAAGUCAUACUUGGGUAGCACAAGCAUGAGAGGCUUCUGCUUCAGUGCUGACCUUCACCAGCAUCAAAAGCAUUACAAUGAAGAAGAGCCCUGGAAAAGGAAGGUGGAUGAGGCUACAUUUGUGACCGGCUGCAGAUUCCAUGUGUUGAAUUAUUUCACCUGUGGGGAGGCCUUCCCAGCCCCCACGGACCUACUCCAACACGAAGCCACUCCCAGUGGUGAGGAGCCACACAGUAGCAGCAGCAAGCAUAUACAGGCAUUUUUCAAUGCAAAAAGUUAUUACAAGUGGGGUGAAUACAGAAAAGCUUCAAGCCACAAACACACACUUGUUCAGCAUCAGAGUGUCUGUUCUGAAGGAGGGCUUUAUGAGUGUAGCAAAUGUGAGAAAGCCUUCACUUGCAAGAACACACUUGUUCAGCACCAGCAAAUUCACACUGGACAAAAGAUGUUUGAGUGUAGUGAAUGUGAGGAAUCCUUUAGCAAAAAGUGCCACCUAAUCUUACACAAGAUAAUUCACACUGGAGAAAGGCCUUAUGAAUGCAGUGAUCGUGAGAAAGCCUUUAUCCAUAAAUCUGAAUUCAUUCACCACCAGAGACGUCACACUGGAGGAGUGCGUCAUGAGUGUGGUGAAUGUAGGAAAACCUUUAGCUACAAAUCUAACCUCAUUGAACACCAGAGAGUUCACACUGGAGAAAGGCCUUAUGAAUGUGGCGAGUGCGGGAAAUCCUUUAGACAAAGCUCUAGCCUUUUUCGACACCAGAGAGUUCACUCUGGAGAAAGGCCUUAUCAGUGCUGUGAGUGUGGGAAAUCCUUUAGACAAAUCUUCAAUCUCAUUCGACAUAGAAGAGUUCACACUGGAGAAAUGCCUUAUCAGUGCAGUGAUUGUGGGAAAUCUUUUAGCUGCAAAUCGGAACUCAUUCAACACCAGAGAAUUCACAGUGGAGAAAGACCUUAUGAAUGCAGAGAAUGUGGGAAAUCCUUUAGACAAUUCUCUAACCUCAUUCGACACCGCAGCAUUCACACUGGUGAUAGGCCUUAUGAGUGCAGUGAAUGUGAGAAAUCCUUUAGCCGCAAAUUUAUCCUGAUUCAACACCAAAGAGUUCACACUGGAGAAAGACCUUAUGAAUGCAGUGAAUGUGGAAAAUCCUUUACCCGCAAAUCUGACCUCAUUCAACACCGGAGAAUUCAUACUGGCACAAGACCUUAUGAGUGCAGUGAAUGUGGCAAAUCUUUUAGACAGCGCUCUGGCCUCAUUCAGCACCGGAGACUUCAUACUGGAGAAAGGCCUUAUGAAUGUAGUGAAUGUGGAAAGUCUUUUAGCCAAAGUGCUAGCCUCAUUCAACACCAGAGAGUUCACACUGGAGAAAGGCCUUAUGAAUGUAGUGAAUGUGGGAAAUCCUUUAGCCAGAGCUCUAGCCUCAUUCAACACCAGAGAGGUCACACUGGAGAAAGACCUUAUGAGUGCAGUCAAUGUGGGAAACCCUUUACCCACAAAUCAGACCUUAUUCAGCACCAAAGAGUUCACACUGGAGAAAGGCCUUAUGAAUGCAGUGAAUGUGGGAAAUCCUUUAGCCGCAAAUCUAACCUCAUUCGACAUCGGAGAGUUCACACUGAAGAAAGGCCUUAAAUGUGAAGGGAAUGUGCUAUUUCUUUAUUCAGUAUAAUAGCACUGGAGGAGACUGUGGUAGCCAUCUUCGUAAAUUUAAACUUUGAGCACCCACAGUGGGGUAUUCUUCAUAAGUUUCAGGUAUGUGGGAAGCUCUGAGGAGGUUCAUUGUAAUUUCUAAUCUGCCGAGGCCUAUAGCCUGAUUUAUGUCACUGCCAAUUUCUGAGGCUGAAGCCAUUUCACAUUUCACCCCUACCACCUGGCAGGUGCACACCAUGUGCAUGAGUCACUUCCCCACAGUGCUCAGAGAAGCAAACCUCUGUACUCUCCCAUUUGCUUGGGGAAAUUAUUAAUAGCCCAAGCAUGUAGGGUCUUCAUGUCUUUUCUCUGACUUUAGAGUAUACACCUGACCCAGUUGUGGUCCAGAGAAUCUGAGUUGUGCUGUCAGCUUUCUAAGGAUUACUUUUUUAAGGAACAUUGUCGGUCUCACAUGAUGCUUGUAAUGAAUUUUUCCACAUUCUGAUUCACCAGCCUGGAAACUGCUUGGUGCACAUUGCUUUAAUUUAUAAUGUUUUUAUAAAGGUUUUAAAAAAAUUUACGCACCUUUAAUCUUGGGUGUUCUAUUCAUUGCAUAGAAUGACUUGUAAGCAGAAUAGUGAUGUCAGCAUGAAGGGGUGAAUAGAUUUUGUGGAGAUCUCAAACUUUCUGUACUCAGAAGGGACAAUGUGAUGGCAGAAGACAGCUCUUUGUUCUGUAUUGCUCUAAUUGGCCUGCUGCCCAAGGCCUCAAAGUAAAGACUGCCAGGCUUUGUGUUCCUGUAUUGUGGCCUGGUGCCAUUUUUGUCAGGUCAGAGGUCACCAUGAAAAGGAGGCAGUUGUGACAAUCCCCAGUGCUUCUGUGAACGUGAAUUUUGUUCAGUUGUCCACAGGAGAUCCACAUAAUUCCUAGCACUGGUGAGGGGAAUCUGUUGCCCAGGUCCUGCAAAGGAGCCAGGUGCCAUGGCAUAUAAGUCAGUGUAGACUGGUGCCAUUUGUUGUCAGACUAUAGGUGUGGAGGUGAAAUUACAGGUUCAACAGUAAUUGGGACAGAAACUCCAGGUAAAUGGGGAGUGGAGAAGACUGCAGUAAAUUAGAUGGAAUGACUCUUCUAAAAGUUCAUCUACAAAUUUUCCAGUGAAUAUGGUUGUGUAGGAUCAGUGCAUACAGAAAUUCUCAGGAUCUUCUGUUUACUAUCGCUGAGAUCAUUAUCAGAAAAUAGUCUGGCCGGGCAUGGUGUAAUCCUAACACUUUGGGAGGCCAAGGCGGGCGGAUUGCCUGAGCUCAGGAGUUCAAGACCAGCCUGGGCAACAUGGUGAAAUCCCAUGUCUACUAAAAUACAAAAAAUUAGCCAGGCGUGGCAGCAUGCGCCUAUAGUCCCAGCCACUUGGGAGGCUGAGGCAGGAGAAUCGCUUGAACCCAGAAGGCGGAAGUUGCAGUGAGCUGAGAUUGCACCACUGCACUCCAGCCCAGGCAACAGAGUGAGACUCCGUCUCCAAAAAAAAAAAAGAAAAUAGUCUAUAAAGGUUUUGUGGCUCCUUGUAUCCUGUCUGGGCUGUUCACCUCAAGGCCAUUGCUAUGCAGGUAGGAGAACAAGAAUAGAGAGAAGGAUCAUUCCGCGGUCCAGGGAUGUGGCUUUUGUGACUCAGCCAACAUUCCUAUUAAUUCAGGUGGCAACAGCCUUCAUUGCUUGCCAAAAUUUGCUGCCCCUGAGGCAAGGUUGCCUCUCUCAGGGCAUGAGGAGAGAGAGAGAUGGUGAAGUCCAUAUCAGGUUGCCACCCUGAUUAAAAAAAAAGGAACAUCUAGGCUCUUAAUUUUGAGCCACUUUUUAAAGCUUUUUGAAGGUCUAAUUUGUAUAACUGACAUGCAACAAAGUACACGUAUCCAAAGUGUACAGUUUGGUAAAGCCAUGAAACCAUCAUUACAACCAUAAAAAUGAAUUUGUGUGUCACCCAUAUAUUUACCUUGUAUCUUUUUAUAAUCUUUCUCCCUUCCCCAGCUCUUCAGGUUCAACUGAUUUCCUUUACAGUAAAUUAGUUUGCAUUUUCUGGAGUUUUUACUGAGAUACAUACACACACACACACACACACACACACACACGUAUACGCAUAUACGUAUACGUAUAUAUAUACAUAUGUGUUUAUAUAUGUGUGUGUGUAUAUAUAUAUACUUACUGGUUUUCUUCAUGCUGUAUAAUUAUUUUGAGAUUCAAAAAUGAUGAAUCUUUGUAUUGCUGAGUAUCAUGCUGUUCUAUGGAUAAGUCAGUGUUUAUCCAUGUGUUUAGGGACAUUUAUAUUAUUUAUAGAUUUUUGUAUAUUACAAAUAAAGCUGCUGUAAAUACUUGAA